GGCGGCCGCGCUGCCUGGCAGCCCGGGAAGCCGCGGCACAGCUGCUCGGCGCCUGCAGCUCCGGCUCGGGGGCUGGAACCGAAGCGGGGGCGGCGGGAGCGCGGAGACCACAGCCCCCGGGGAGAGGCGGAGGGGGUCCCUGGCCUGGGCGGAGAGGCUGAGCUGAGUGCGCGUGAGAAAGAGGGCUGCACCGCUGCUCGGCGCGGACUCUGCCAGCCCCAGCUUCAGCCCCGGCUCAGGUCGCCGCAGCCCGGGAGCCUCCCCGCUUGCGCCCCAAGGCACGCGCGGCACAGCCAUGAACACCAACGAUGCCAAGGAGUAUCUGGCCCGGAGGGAAAUCCCUCAGCUUUUUGAGAGCCUUUUGAAUGGACUGAUGUGUUCUAAGCCCGAAGAUCCAGUAGAAUACUUGGAAAGUUGUUUACAAAAAGUAAAGGAACUGGGUGGCUGUGACAAGGUGAAAUGGGAUACAUUUGUAAGCCAGGAAAAGAAGACCUUACCUCCACUAAAUGGAGGACAGUCACGGAGAUCCUUUCUAAGAAAUGUAAUGCCUGAAAACUCAAACUUUCCAUAUCGGCGGUAUGACCGGCUCCCUCCAAUCCAUCAAUUCUCCAUAGAAAGUGACACGGAUCUCUCUGAGACUGCAGAGUUGAUUGAGGAGUAUGAGGUUUUUGAUCCUACCAGACCUCGACCAAAAAUCAUUCUUGUUAUAGGUGGUCCAGGAAGUGGAAAGGGUACUCAGAGUUUGAAAAUUGCAGAACGAUAUGGAUUCCAAUACAUUUCUGUGGGAGAAUUAUUAAGAAAGAAGAUCCACAGUACCAGCAGCAAUAGGAAAUGGAGUCUUAUUGCCAAGAUAAUUACAACUGGAGAAUUGGCCCCACAGGAAACAACAAUUACAGAGAUAAAACAAAAAUUGAUGCAAAUACCUGAUGAAGAGGGCAUUGUUAUUGAUGGAUUUCCAAGAGAUGUUGCCCAGGCUCUAUCUUUUGAGGACCAAAUCUGUACCCCCGAUUUGGUGGUAUUCCUGGCUUGUGCUAAUCAGAGACUCAAAGAAAGAUUACUGAAGCGUGCAGAACAGCAGGGCCGACCAGACGACAAUGUAAAAGCUACCCAAAGGAGACUAAUGAACUUCAAGCAGAAUGCUGCUCCAUUGGUUAAAUACUUCCAGGAAAAGGGGCUCAUCAUGACAUUUGAUGCCGACCGCGAUGAGGAUGAGGUGUUCUAUGACAUCAGCAUGGCAGUUGACAACAAGUUAUUUCCAAACAAAGAGGCUGCAGCAGGUUCAAGUGACCUUGAUCCUUCGAUGAUAUUGGACACUGGAGAGAUCAUUGAUACAGGAUCUGAUUAUGAAGAUCAGGGUGAUGACCAGUUAAAUGUAUUUGGAGAGGACACUAUGGGAGGUUUCAUGGAAGAUUUGAGAAAGUGUAAAAUUAUUUUCAUAAUUGGACCAUGCUCACCAAAACAAUAGGAAGAAGAUGCUCAUCUGUGGAGUGGCUGUUACCAACUAUGUCCAUGGCAGCAGCAGAGUUUAGCUGCACCUCCCAGAGGCCUACAGUUUACUCUCAAAGUGAGAACAUAGCAAGUAGGCAGAAGCUGCACCCCUGCUUUUGAAGUCCUUCUUUUGGAGCUGCCCAACAAUCCCUCUUGGACUACUCACCAAAGCCCCAGGAAUGCCACCCCCUCUCACACCCUGCUGUGGUAUAGGUGAACUCAGGUGGCACUGUCCUAGCCUUGAGCCCUAGUAGAAGACGCUGGCUGCAUCCACUUGGUCUCCCCAGCAGAGGAGAUGGUGUGUUUCUAUUGGGCAUCUGUUGUCCAUAGGAAAGUCUUCCUAAGACUGCGUCAAAACCUGCUCUGUCAGAAAUUCCAAUAUUUAGGCAUUUCUGUCUGGUGUCCUAGGCUCUAUAUCUAGUACAUAAUUAAAAUCACCUAUCAGGUUUUUCACCAAAGAUAAAAAUUGCUGAGAGUUAACAUUGUAACAUGUAAUUAAGACUACUAAAAACCAUCAGUUUCACAUGCCAGGCCUGUGAGGAAGUGAAAUGUGCUUUUAGUAAAAGAUUAUAAGAAGAUACGGGAAUGUACAUUUUUGCCUAGUUUAGAGGGCUAAAGGAUUGUUUUAAAUUAGAUAUGAUAAACCUAAAUGUUUGAGCAAGUUUUGGAAGGUUUGUGAAAAAUUAAUUGUAAAAGAGAUUCUGUGUAUGAACAUAUUGGCUAAAUUUAAAGGGGUAUUAUUCAGUUUUUUCCAUGCUUUUGGAAUAAAGCACAACAUGGUUUUCUUAGAGCAUGGAUCUGCUCUUUAACAAGAAUUUGUAAAGGGUUAUAAAAGGUUUAUGAGAAGCUCACCUUAUGGUUAAACUGAUUAAGACUGGAUAGAUUUGUCUAUAAGGUUUUAUUAAAAAUUGGGGUGGAGGCCGGGCACAGUGGCUCAAACCUAUAAUCCCAGCACUUUGGGAGGCCGAGGCAGACGGAUCACCUGAGGUCAGGAGUUCGAGACCAGCCUAGCCAACAUGGUGAAACCCUGUCUCUACUAAAUAUACCAAAAAAAUGAGCCAGGUGUGGUGGCGGGCGCCUGCAAUCCCAGCUACUCAGAAGGCUGAGGCAGGAGAAUUGCUUGAACCCAGGAGGUGGAGGUUGCAGUGAGCCGAGAUUGUGCCACUGUACUCCAGCCUGGGUGACAAGAGACUGUCUCAAAAAAAAAAGAAAAAAAAAUGGGGUUGAAAAAAAUUUUUCACUGUUUAGUCUAGUCCUGCCAUACAGAGAAAAUUAGCUUUCUCUCCACCCUGCCGAUUCAAAUAUUUGAAGACAUAUACACUUUUCUUGUGAUUUAUGUCUUCAUCCAAUUAAAAACAUGCAGCUUUUUCUGUUGUAAAUUGCAGGUUCCUCAAGAGCAGAGUGCUAUCUUCUUGUCUCUGUGUCCCCAGUCCUUACACUGCCUAGCGCAUGUGGAUUCCUCACAUUUUCUUGUGGAAUGAAUGAAUAAAUUCUACUUUUAUUAUUUCCCCCUAAGUCAUGUCUCUUUAGACACAUGCAGCCCAAAUCUCUCCUAAAACAGAUUGGCGAGAACAUUUUUAAAUUUAAGGAUUUCUUUUCUUUUUACAAAAAAUAAUACAUCUUCAUUCUAGAAAACGUGUAUCAACAAUAACAAAAUCACAAACAGCCCAAUACCUGGGAAUGAAUACUAUUAGUAUUUUGAUUUAUAUUCCUCUUAGUUUUUUUCUGUGUAUAUAUAUAUUUUUUUUAAUAUACAUUUUUCAUCAGAAUGAGAUCAUAUAAUUUAAAAACCUACUUUUUAUACUUAACAAAACCUCAUGGGCAUCUUUCCAAGAUAGUAUUCCUGAAUAUGCCAUGUCAUUUUUUAAAGUUCUUUUGUAAUUCAACCGAAAUACAAAAACAGAAAAGUGCACAAGUCUUAAGUAUUCUGUUUGAUGAAAUUUCACUAAUUGGACGCAUGUGUCUUACCAAGAUGAAGAUCAGAAAAUUGAACGUGACCAGAACCUCAGAAAUCUCCCUUGUGUCUCCUCCUCAUCACUACUCCCUGCAAGGACUACCAUAGGCAUUUUUUAACUUCCAUAGAUGGAAUCACACUAUAUAACUGUAUAUAUUAUUUUCUAGCUGUCUUCUUUCAGCACAUCAUUUUAAUGACUGCAUCCUAUUCCUUUAUUUUGCUGUAAUAGAAUUUAUUCAGUUUAUACCUAUGAUUGUGUUGUCAUAAUACAUUAUUUUUUCAACUUUUGCUUUUAUUAAAAAUUCUGUAAUGAA